GGACGGAGGGACGGGGGCUCAAGGGCGGGUCGGGUGGGGUCCCGACGCCCCCUCCUCGGCUGGGCGCACCCCGGGUGUCCGCAGGGAGGGGCGAUGUUCUGGGGGGGGGAGCGUCUGCCCGACGCCCCCUCCCUCAGGAGCUCCUUCCCUUAACAGAGCUGAGAGAGGCAUCUGGAGCUGCAGCAUGGACCAGCGAGAGCCCCUGCCUCCCGCUCCUGCAGAAAAUGAAAUGAAAUAUGAUACCAAUAAUAAUGAAGAGGAAGAGGGAGAACAGUUCGAUUUUGACAGUGGAGAUGAAAUCCCAGAAGCGGACAGACAGGCCCCAUCCGCCCCUGAGACAGGAGGUGCUGGAGCCAGUGAAGCCCCUGCACCCACAGGAGGUGAGGAUGGAGCUGGAGCAGAAACCACCCCAGUGGCAGAGCCUACUAAGCUGGUGCUCCCGAUGAAAGUCAACCCAUAUUCUGUCAUCGACAUCACGCCAUUCCAGGAGGACCAGCCGCCCACCCCCGUGCCCAGCGCUGAGGAGGAGAAUGUGGGUCUCCAUGUGCCCUGCGGGUACUUGGUGCCUGUACCCUGCGGCUAUGCGGUGCCCUCCAACCUGCCCCUCCUGCUGCCCGCCUACUCCAGCCCGGUCAUCAUCUGCGCCACGUCCCUGGACGAAGAAGAAACACCAGAAGUCACAGAAGAUCGCCAGCCCAAUUCUCUGAGUUCCGAGGAGCCUCCAACCAGUGAAGAUCAAGUCGGUCGAGAGGACAGCGCACUUGCCCGCUGGGCCGCAGACCCGGCCAACACAGCCUGGAUGGAGAAUCCAGAGGAAGCAAUUUACGAUGACGUUCCAAGGGAAAACUCAGACUCUGAACCAGAUGAAAUGAUUUAUGAUGAUGUUGAGAAUGGGGAUGAAGGUGGAAACAGCUCCUUGGAAUACGGAUGGAGUUCGAGUGAAUUUGAAAGUUACGAAGAGCAGAGUGACUCGGAGUGCAAGAAUGGGAUUCCCAGGUCCUUCCUGCGCAGCAACCACAAAAAGCAACUUUCUCAUGACCUAACCCGUUUAAAGGAGCACUAUGAGAAAAAGAUGAGAGAUUUGAUGGCAAGCACGGUGGGCGUGGUGGAGAUUCAGCAGCUCAGGCAGAAGCAUGAACUGAAGAUGCAGAAGCUCGUGAAGGCCGCGAAGGACGGCACCAAGGACGGGCUGGAGAGGACCAGGGCAGCCGUGAAGAGGGGCCGCUCCUUCAUCAGGACCAAGUCUCUCAUCGCACAGGAUCACAGAUCUUCUCUUGAGGAAGAACAGAAUUUGUUCAUUGAUGUUGACUGCAAGCACCCGGAAGCCAUCUUGACCCCGAUGCCCGAGGGUUUAUCUCAGCAGCAGGUUGUAAGAAGAUAUAUACUGGGUUCAGUUGUCGACAGUGAAAAGAACUACGUAGAUGCUCUUAAGAGGAUUUUGGAGCAAUAUGAGAAGCCGCUGUCUGAGAUGGAGCCAAAGGUUCUGAGUGAGAGGAAGCUGAAGACGGUGUUCUACCGAGUCAAAGAGAUCCUGCAGUGCCACUCGCUAUUUCAGAUCGCGCUGGCCAGCCGCGUUUCCGAGUGGGACUCCGUGGAAAUGAUAGGCGAUGUCUUCGUGGCUUCGUUUUCUAAGUCCAUGGUGCUGGAUGCAUACAGUGAAUAUGUGAACAAUUUCAGCACAGCCGUGGCAGUCCUCAAGAAAACAUGUGCCACAAAGCCCGCUUUUCUUGAAUUUUUAAAGCAGGAACAGGAGGCCAGCCCCGAUCGAACCACGCUCUACAGCCUGAUGAUGAAGCCCAUCCAGAGGUUCCCACAGUUCAUCCUCCUGCUCCAGGACAUGCUGAAGAACACCUCCAAAGGCCACCCCGACAGGCUGCCUCUUCAGAUGGCCCUGACAGAGCUCGAAACACUAGCAGAGAAGUUAAAUGAAAGAAAGAGAGAUGCUGAUCAACGCUGUGAAGUGAAGCAAAUAGCCAAAGCCAUAAACGAAAGAUACCUGAACAAGCUUCUCAGCAGUGGAAGCCGAUACCUCAUUCGAUCAGAUGAUAUGAUAGAAACAGUUUACAACGACAGAGGAGAGAUUGUUAAAACCAAAGAACGCCGAGUCUUCAUGUUAAAUGAUGUGUUAAUGUGUGCCACCGUCAGCUCACGCCCCUCUCAUGACAGCCGUGUGAUGAGCAGCCAGAGGUACUUGCUGAAGUGGAGCGUUCCACUGGGACAUGUGGACGCCAUCGAGUAUGGCAGCAGCGCAGGCACGGGCGAGCACAGCAGGCACCUUGCCGUUCACCCGCCGGAGAGCCUGGCCGUGGUUGCUAACGCGAAACCAAACAAAGUUUACAUGGGGCCAGGACAACUGUAUCAAGAUUUACAAAACUUGUUGCAUGACUUAAAUGUAAUUGGCCAAAUCACUCAGCUGAUAGGAAACCUUAAAGGAAACUAUCAGAACUUAAACCAGUCAGUAGCCCAUGACUGGACAUCAGGUUUACAAAGGCUUAUUUUGAAGAAAGAAGAUGAAAUCAGAGCUGCGGACUGCUGCAGAAUUCAGUUACAGCUUCCCGGGAAGCAGGACAAAUCUGGGCGACCGACGUUCUUUACAGCUGUGUUCAAUACGUUCACCCCUGCCAUCAAGGAGUCCUGGGUCAACAGCUUACAGAUGGCCAAGCUCGCCCUAGAAGAGGAGAACCACAUGGGCUGGUUCUGUGUGGAAGACGAUGGGAAUCACAUUAAAAAGGAGAAGCAUCCUCUCCUCGUCGGACACAUGCCCGUGAUGGUGGCCAAGCAGCAGGAGUUCAAGAUUGAAUGUGCUGCUUAUAACCCUGAACCUUACCUAAAUAAUGAAAGCCAGCCAGAUUCAUUUUCCACGGCACAUGGUUUCCUGUGGAUCGGAAGUUGCACCCAUCAAAUGGGUCAGAUUGCCAUCGUCUCGUUUCAAAAUUCCACUCCCAAAGUCAUUGAGUGCUUCAACGUGGAAUCUCGCAUCCUGUGCAUGCUGUACGUUCCCGUCGAGGAGAAGCGCAGAGAGCCUGGGGCACCCCCGGACCCCGAGACCCCGGCCGUGAGAGCUUCUGAUGUCCCCACGAUCUGUGUAGGGACGGAGGAGGGAAGCAUUUCCAUUUAUAAAAGCAGUCAAGGCUCCAAGAAAGUGAGACUUCAGCACUUUUUCACUCCUGAGAAGUCCACAGUCAUGAGCCUGGCUUGCACGUCUCAGAGCCUGUACGCUGGCCUGGUCAACGGGGCAGUCGCCAGCUACGCCAGAGCCCCAGAUGGAUCCUGGGAUUCAGAACCUCAAAAAGUGAUCAAGUUAGGCGUCCUACCAGUUAGAAGUCUACUCAUGAUGGAAGACACGUUGUGGGCGGCUUCCGGAGGUCAAGUCUUCAUCAUCAGUGUGGAGACUCAUGCUGUAGAGGGUCAGCUGGAGGCCCACCAGGAGGAAGGCAUGGUGAUCUCCCACAUGGCCGUGUCCGGCGUCGGGAUCUGGAUUGCCUUCACCUCAGGGUCCACGCUCCGCCUUUUUCACACGGAAACUCUCAAGCACCUGCAGGACAUCAACAUCGCCACCCCUGUUCACAACAUGCUGCCAGAGUUCCGAGAGCAGCCACGGAAAUGCAGCGGCCCUGCAGGAUCCUUGGUGUUUAUCCCUCUCCGGGUGGGAUCAGAAAGAAACUCCUAAUCAAGGGAAGGCUCUGGCAAGUGUGAGUGGAGUUUGUAUUUUGAAUUUGAUUUCUUAAUAAAAUAACCCUUGCACACGAUUUAAUAAAACCCAACAGCACUCACGCCCAGGCUAUGAAAAGCAAAGCAGGAUAGGAAAGCCUGCGCUCUGGGGACUCACAGCCCCGCCCCCAUCCCAGCACCCCACCCACUGUCAGCACCCAACCCUGCCCCCAUCCUCACACCCCACCCCGCAUUCAGCACCCACCCUCUCAUCCCAGCAUCCCACCCACUGUCAGCACCCGCCCCGGCCCCCCGCACUGUCCCCAUACCCCACCCCGCUGUCAGCUGCCUCUCCCGCCCGCCUCCCUACUGCUGCUGCUCGAAAGCCACUCCUGUAUGGCAGGUUCUUGAUGCUUUGUUUUAGAUACUGUCUUUGACCUCUCCUGUAGAAGAGAAAGAUGGAAUUAUCCUGCUUCCCUCCAAGCAUAGAGCACCCAACACAGUCCUGCACCCACCCAGAAACAGAAUGCAGACCCCUUGCCGGCUGCUCAGGUCGCAGGUUCUGGCUAAAUCGCAGCUGCCUGUGUUGCGUGUUUUGGAUGAUGAAGUUGUCUGUGGCUGGGCGCUGAGCCUUCCUUGGGACUUUUCACCCUUCAGCUCAUAGUUUCCAGGCGGCCGAUGAUGGAUCCAUCCCAAGCCCACCACAAGCCUCUCACUUGGCAGCAGAUGCAUGGGGCUCUGCAGAGCCACCAUCCCCUGGCGCCCACUCUCCCGGGCCCCUCCAACAUCCUGGGCUGGCUCUCCAUGGCCACAGUGCGUGCUCUCAGCCCCCUGCUCCGGGGGCCCCUGAAUCGUGGGUCUUUACUUAUUCCUACACGACAUAGUCAGGUCUGCAUUUUAGACCCGCAUGAAAGCAAACACAUGAGUCUGUCCAGAUGGAGUGCCGUGCUUCUCGUUGGCAGGUUUCUCCGGCAUUUCGGUACUAAGUUGGAAAUAGCUCCAGCUUCACUGAUUUCUGGGGUACACUGACUGCUUUACCCACAUUCAGUUCUCUGCUCCCAGGCUGUGGUCUGCUGCCACCGUGGCCUUGUCAGCAGGAGAAAGGUACACGGGUUAGAGGCAACCUCGGUGACACCAGAAGUUCAGUUUUGUUUGUGAUGCUUCUGACAGUGAUUCUCUGUAAGAUCCUCAGUGCGGCAUAGACUGAAAUGGUUCUGAUUUUCAUUGCAUUUUGUGACUCAGAGGGAAUGAGCAGGCCAGAGAGUCCUUUCCUCCAGAGAGUCCUUUCAUCUCAUCUCCUCUGUCUAGUCGUCUUUGCCUUUCAGCUAAUAUUUCAUAUAUUUCAUAGAAAUAAGCAUUAUUGCAUUUCAUGCUGUAUUUAGACAUUCCGGUGGGGGCAUGCUCAUACCGUGCUGAAGUGCGCGGAUGCUGAGGUCGCCGGGCCGUCACUGCUCCUGGGUUCUUCUCCUCCUUAUCGUCCAAGAUGGUUCCUGGAGGCCCACACAUGUCCUCUGUGCUCUGUUCGCACACACACAAAACCUUCAUUCUAGAGUUGUAUUCAUGACGAUGCUCAAAUGGGUUUUCAUGUGUGUGUGUGUGUGUGUGUGUGGCAACAAGACAUAAAAUUAUCUUUUUGUGCUAUUGCUGGAAUAUAAAAGUCAGGUAGCUUCUGCAAAUGAAGACUUGCCAAGCCGAAACAACAAAAUUUGAAAAAAACAAACUGUAUUAUAACUCAUGCCUUUUGUGUAAGUUCACACAACGUGAUGAAACCUCCUUCCUUCCUCAGGGUCUCAGCACGCUGGCCCCUGGGGAAUCCGUGAAUCUGUAGCUAAGGCCCUGGCUUUUCUCCUUCUAUUUGGAAUUCACUUCUGAAAACCAUUUAGCUCACGUUCUUUCACAUAAGCUACAUCAGAUUCAACACAGACUAACAGUUGAUGAAGGUCUGUGAUUAACAUACACAUUCGUUAGAGCGGUCGUUACCUUUCUAAGUUAUAAAGGAGUAGAGUUUACAGCGAGUGAGUUCACGGCGCCUCAGCUUUUAGGUUGUGAGCAGUUGCAGUAGGUUACAUCACCAGGCAGAUGUUUCCUGCUCUGUCCCGCAUGUUCAAAGGAGGAUAUUUUUGAUGGGAAAGUGCUGAGACACAUGGUAAAUUGCGCCUUUCUGAGUCUCCACCGAGCGAAUACAGAGCCUCCAGGAACUAUGUGACCAAAUAAAAUGGCCAAAAUUUCCAUUAGAAAAAAAAAGACAAAAAACGUGUAACUUUUCUGAAGACCAUGGACUACACCGUAAGGGAAUUCAGUAAAUGAAACCGGACUCAAGAUGGUGAGUUAACGAACGAGACUGAGGACUUGGGAGCCACAGCCUUUCUCGGUGGCCGGUGUGGCCCUGGCCUGUCCUUUGUUUUAUGUUCCAGGCUGGGAAGAGCAGAGGGCGAAUCCCCCUGGUAGCAUUCCCUCCCAUACUUGGGGGACGUAUUGCUUCUUCUACUCACUGUUCUGUCUCUGAGGUUAUUUGAAUGAACCUGGAUGGUGUUGUUUACACCCCCAGCUUCUCCCAGCCUCCAGGGCGGGAGAUGCGUCUGCCUCUGUGGCUGCCUGCAGAAGGCCCUGGUGACUCCCCACGGAGUCACCAUCCAGCAGCCGCUCAAGUGCAGUCAGUCCCACUUCACACGUGUAACCCAUUUACCAACCUCACUGUGCAGCUGCAUCACCGUUCACCACCUCAGCUGCCCCUGCCUCCCACCUCGCCAGCGGACCUCACGUGGGCUCCAACUCCCGGGACCCAGCCCCAUCUGGGACACGCCCUGCUGUCCUGUUCUAGGUCACUGUUGGUGCUUCCGGACGGGCACGGGACGCCUGGAUAGCGGCACUCACCGCAGCCUCUGGAAUCGGAAAAUGACCGCAUGACCUCGUGACUGUGGCCCUCAGCUUUCCCAUGUAAAAUUAAAGAUGUUGAUUGGCAGACUGCUUGGAAAAUGCAAUGGAAAACCACUCUCUGGAACUUAACUCUUUUACGUCGUUCCUGGGUACUUUGAAACCAGUUAAAAACAUUCAUAUCGGGUUUCUACCUGCUUUUACCCUUUUUAUUAUUUAUUUAUUUAUUUAUUUAUUUAUUUGAAACGGAGUUUCACUCCUUUUGCCCAGGCUGGAGUGCAGUGGUGCGAUCUUGGCUCACUGCAACCUCCGCCUCCCGGGUUCAAGCAAUUCUCCUGCCUCAGCUCCUGAGUAGUUGGGAUAACAGGUGCCUACCACCACGCCCAGCUAGUUUUUUUGUAUUUUUUUGUUUUGUUUUUUAGGUUUUUUUUUUUUUUUUUUUUUGUAUUUUUAGUAGGGAUGGGGUUUCACUAUGUUGGCCAGGCUGGUCUGGAACUCCUGGCCUCAGGGGAUCCACCCACCUCGGCCUCCCAAAGUGCUGGGAUUACAGGCAUGAGCCACUGCGCCCGGCCUACCCUUUUUAUUAAAUGCAAGCUUUGGCCAGCAUUACAGGAGCCCUUCCAGAAGCCGGGCCAUCGUUUCAGUCACGCAGCCGCAGCCUUGCCCGGCACGCAGGUGGGGCUUCUCCCCUUCCCAGUAUCUCACAUCCCUGCUCCCACAGCGGGGCUGCUUCCCAUCCUAGUGCCACACGGAGGGCCGGGGAGGCCGGGUUCAGGUUUGAUGCUGAACUCAUAUGCACACCGGUUUUCUCUCUCAUAAGACAAUCAUGUUUCAUGCUUAAAAUACUUACUGUUGAGUCAAACUGCUGCUCUAGAAAGAUCAUCCACACUCCCUUUGCGGCUGCGCCCCGGGCUGCUCCCCGUGUUGUAGAGCGGUCAGCACUUCGGAGCAGCUGGGAAUCGCGUACCCUGCGUAUCAGCUUUGAAGCUGCUGCCGUGUUUCUCAUUAGCUUUAGAAAGUAACAGCACCGGCUUACGUACAGGACAGCGCUGUGGAUUCACUAUCGCCCUGACCAAGUCACGCCGACCAGGCCAACAUUCAGAAUUCCUGGGACAUGCAUAUUAUUGAGCUUUUAAAAAUAAUAUGAAUCGGCGUUUAGAAAUAGAACCAAAUGUCUUUCUUUUUCUGUAGUGAGGGUUUUUUGUUUUGGGGGAGGCUGUUUGACCUCUGUCGAUACGGAGUCUUUGGCUCUGGUGUGAGGUUGUUUUUCAUGCUCUUUAUCAGAGAUGAACUUUGGGUCAAAUGCAGGGAUAUUUAAAAUAGCUUUUAUAUCUACAGAAAAGAAUCAAACUGUUUUUAAGUGUUCACCGUCACUUCUCAGGAGCAAGCUAAAUGGGCCUACUGUGCUCCUCAGCUUUGGGGCUAAACAGAGAAACACUGGGGAUUAGCUUUUCUGUGUGUGAAGGCCGCGAUGCUGACGAUUGUGUCAGAGUUGUGGUGGAAUGAUGUGACAGUCCAGACCCACCCUGAAACCACAGUGAGGCGGGGUCUUUGGAGCAGGUGAUGUGGCUCCCACCCUGUAACUGCAGUGAGGUGGGGUCUUCCUUGUAGCCACCGUGAGGCGGGGUCUUCCCUGUAACCGCCGUGAGGCGGGGUCUUGGAAUAGGCCAUGCGUCUCCCACAUUGUUUUGCAGCCACUUUCUAGCCUUGUCACUGCCGGAGCAAAUUGUUUAGUUUCUCUGGGCUUCAGAUCCUUGGCUGUAAAGCAAAUCAAAACCAAACUAACAAAGAGCCUCAAAGGCCCUUCUCACCCCACCAUCCACCGUGAUGUUUCCCUGCUGUGUCCAGCGCUGAGGCUGUGUGACGAUGUUGUUCUUCACGCAGAGCCCUGGAGAGGCCGUUCAGUUCCCCUCUAGGGUCCAACUGCGGCUGAGGGCCGGUUACUCGAGUCCAGCCGCGCCCAUUAAGAGACCUCUCCUCACUUGUAAAGGGGUCUCUCUGCUCCCAAAGAACCACAGGCCGCUGUGUAUGUCGGGGGCUCACGAGCUCACGUGCUACACGGCCCAGAAGCAAAAGGUUUAGACAGAUUCAUCCAGGGGCUUGAUUCAUGGCUGAAGCGGCCAAGCAGAGCCAUGCAGACGACAGCCCAGGAGACCCAACCAGACAUCUGGCCUGUUCUGUUCAGGUGCAGGUGCAGGGUAUGCCCUCAAGACCCUUGUCUUGCUCAUGUGGUUGAGGGAGCCUGGUGCUCGGGUUUGGGAACUCCUGUGCCACAUCCUGCCCCUGGCGGAUUUGGUGGUGGCACGACAGGCCUGUGGGGUUUCCAGCACCCCGUCACCGCCCCACCAACUCUGCUACACAAACCAGACCCGAAGCCACU